CUGCCCCGCCAUGACCCGGCUGACAGUCCUGGCCCUGCUGGCUGGUCUGCUGGCGUCCUCGAGGGCCGGCUCCAGCCCCCUUUUGGACAUCGUUGGCGGCCGGAAGGCGAGGCCCCGCCAGUUCCCGUUCCUGGCCUCCAUUCAGAAUCAAGGCAGGCACUUCUGCGGGGGUGCCCUGAUCCAUGCCCGCUUCGUGAUGACCGCGGCCAGCUGCUUCCAAAGCCAGAACCCCGGGGUUAGCACCGUGGUGCUGGGUGCCUAUGACCUGAGGCGGCGGGAGAGGCAGUCCCGCCAGACGUUUUCCAUCAGCAGCAUGAGCGAGAAUGGCUACGACCCCCAGCAGAACCUGAACGACCUGAUGCUGCUUCAGCUGGACCGUGAGGCCAACCUCACCAGCAGCGUGACGAUACUGCCACUGCCUCUGCAGAACGCCACGGUGGAAGCCGGCACCAGAUGCCAGGUGGCCGGCUGGGGGAGCCAGCGCAGUGGGGGGCGUCUCUCCCGUUUUCCCAGGUUUGUCAACGUGACUGUGACCCCCGAGGACCAGUGUCGCCCCAACAACGUGUGCACCGGUGUGCUCACCCGCCGCGGUGGCAUCUGCAAUGGGGACGGGGGCACCCCCCUCGUCUGCGAGGGCCUGGCCCACGGCGUGGCCUCCUUUUCCCUGGGGCCCUGUGGCCGAGGCCCUGACUUCUUCACCCGAGUGGCGCUCUUCCGAGACUGGAUCGAUGGUGUUCUCAACAACCCGGGACCGGGGCCAGCCUAGGGGGGCCUGUGACCUCCCAUGGAGCCCAGCCCCGCCCUCCACACCUCCGGCGCUCCGCACCCACCUCCCACGGCCCCGCCCCUGCCCCCGCUCCGGCCAGAGGGGCCCUGGCUGUAAUAAAGAAGCCGAUCUCUCCUCUGC